ACAAUGAGAUCCUAAGAUGGCGGUGGCUGCGGCGGUUGGCGCUGCGUAGCUGAGGUCGAAAAGGCGGCCACUGGGGCCGAGGCAGCCAGGAAACGUGUGGGCCUCUCUGCUGCGGUCUCCGAGGGCCGACCGCUGCCGGCGGCGGGUCGUGGGGGCUGACUGUCGCUCUGCCUUUGACAGGAGAGGCUGCUUCUUGUAGAGGAAACAGCUUUGAAGUGUGGAGCGGGAAAGGAGCAGUUUCUGAGCUGCAAAAACUAGUUUCUAAACAGCUAGCACCCUUUCAACCUGUACAAUUCCACAGCUAGUGGAAAUCCAAAGUCUUCUGCAAGAUUAUGCAGAAAUCUUACUUUCUGAUGAUCAUCUCUGCCUUUGAACCUCUACUUCCACCAUUGCUGCUGCUUUUUCUCAUCUCUUUGACCCAGAGCAGUUCUCCCGUCUUUGACUCUUUGGCAUACAACUAAUGCCUGUGUUUUCAGGGUAUCAUCUUCAUCCCAAGUCCAUUGUCAGAACAGAGAUACUUUCUUUCCUGGGAGAAGUUCUGGGUCUAGCUGUUUAUGACACUUUUCCUACUUUAUUGUUCUACCCUUUGGAACUGUGUUGAAUUAAAGAGUUAAUUGUUAAAUCCAGUAUGGCCACAGGAGGAGGUCCCUUUGAAGAUGGCAUGAAUGAUCAGGAUUUACCAAACUGGAGUAAUGAGAAUGUUGAUGACAGGCUCAACAAUAUGGAUUGGGGUGCCCAACAGAAGAAAGCAAAUAGAUCAUCAGAAAAGAAUAAGAAAAAGUUUGGUGUAGAAAGUGAUAAAAGAGUAACCAAUGAUAUUUCUCCGGAGUCGUCACCAGGAGUUGGAAGGCGAAGAACAAAGACUCCACAUACGUUCCCACACAGUAGAUACAUGAGUCAGAUGUCUGUCCCAGAGCAGGCAGAAUUAGAGAAACUGAAACAGCGGAUAAACUUCAGUGAUUUAGAUCAGAGAAGCAUUGGAAGUGAUUCCCAAGGUAGAGCAACAGCUGCUAACAACAAACGUCAGCUUAGUGAAAACCGAAAGCCCUUCAACUUUUUGCCUAUGCAGAUUAAUACUAACAAGAGCAAAGAUGCAUCUACAAACCCCCCAAACAGAGAAACGAUUGGAUCAGCACAGUGUAAAGAGUUGUUUGCUUCUGCUUUAAGUAAUGACCUCUUGCAAAACUGUCAGGUGUCUGAAGAAGAUGGGAGGGGAGAACCUGCAAUGGAGAGCAGCCAGAUUGUAAGCAGGCUUGUUCAAAUUCGCGAUUAUAUUACUAAAGCUAGUUCCAUGCGGGAAGAUCUUGUAGAGAAAAAUGAGAGAUCUGCUAAUGUUGAGCGCCUUACUCAUCUAAUAGAUCACCUUAAAGAACAAGAGAAGUCAUAUAUGAAAUUUCUUAAAAAAAUCCUUGCUAGAGAAAAUGAGGAGGAGGAUGUUCGGACUAUAGAUUCAGCUGUGGGAUCUGGUUCUGUAGCUGAGAGCACAUCGCUAAACAUAGAUGUGCAGUCUGAGGCUUCAGAUACCACGGCCAGAGAUCCUCAGCAGGAGCCUAUGGAAGAGAUAGAAAAUUUGAAGAAACAACAUGAUUUAUUAAAAAGAAUGUUACAACAGCAGGAGCAACUAAGAGCUCUACAGGGACGGCAGGCUGCACUUCUAGCUCUGCAACAUAAAGCAGAGCAAGCUAUUGCAGUGAUGGAUGAUUCUGUUGUUGCAGAAACUGCAGGUAGCUUAUCUGGCGUCAGUAUCACAUCUGAACUAAAUGAAGAAUUGAAUGACUUAAUUCAGCGUUUUCAUAAUCAGCUUCGUGAUUCUCAGCCUCCAGCUGUUCCAGACAAUAGAAGACAGGCAGAAAGUCUUUCAUUAACUAGGGAGGUUUCCCAGAGCAGGAAACCAUCAGCUUCAGAACGUUUACCUGAUGAGAAAGUCGAACUUUUUAGCAAAAUGAGAGUGCUACAGGAAAAGAAACAAAAAAUGGACAAAUUGCUUGGAGAACUUCAUACACUUCGAGAUCAGCAUCUUAACAAUUCAUCAUCCUCUCCACAAAGGAGUGUCGAUCAGAGAAGUACUUCAGCUCCCUCUGCUUCUGUAGGCUUGGCACCGGUUGUCAAUGGAGAAUCCAAUAGCCUCACAUCAUCUGUUCCUUAUCCUACUGCUUCUCUAGUAUCUCAGAAUGAGAGUGAAAACGAAGGCCACCUCAAUCCAUCUGAAAAACUCCAGAAGUUAAAUGAAGUUCGAAAGAGAUUGAAUGAGCUAAGAGAAUUAGUUCAUUAUUAUGAACAAACGUCAGACAUGAUGACAGAUGCUGUGAAUGAAAACAGGAAAGAUGAAGAAACUGAAGAGUCAGAAUAUGAUUCUGAGCAUGAAAAUUCCGAGCCUGUUACUAACAUUCGAAAUCCACAAGUAGCUUCCACUUGGAAUGAAGUAAAUAGUCAUAGUAAUGCACAGUGUGUUUCUAAUAAUAGAGAUGGGCGAACAGUUAAUUCUAAUUGUGAAAUUAACAACAGAUCUGCUGCCAACAUAAGGGCUCUAAACAUGCCUCCUUCUUUAGAUUGUCGAUAUAAUAGAGAAGGGGAACAGGAGAUUCAUGUUGCACAAGGUGAAGAUGAUGAGGAGGAGGAGGAAGAAGCAGAAGAGGAGGGAGUCAGUGGAGCUUCAUUAUCUAGUCACAGGAGCAGUCUGGUUGAUGAGCAUCCAGAAGAUGCUGAAUUUGAACAGAAGAUCAACCGACUUAUGGCUGCAAAACAGAAACUUAGACAGUUACAAGAUCUUGUUGCUAUGGUACAGGAUGAUGAUGCAGCUCAAGGAGUUAUCUCUGCCAGUGCAUCAAAUUUGGAUGAUUUCUACCCAGCAGAAGAAGACACCAAGCAAAAUUCAAAUAACACUAGAGGAAAUGCCAAUAAAACACAGAAAGAUACUGGAGUAAAUGAAAAGGCAAGAGAGAAAUUUUAUGAGGCUAAACUACAGCAGCAACAGAGAGAGCUAAAACAAUUGCAGGAAGAAAGAAAGAAACUGAUUGACAUUCAGGAGAAAAUUCAAGCAUUGCAAACGGCAUGCCCUGACUUACAGCUGUCAGCUGCUAGUGUGGGUAACUGUCCCACCAAAAAAUAUAUGCCAGCUGUUACUUCAACCCCAACUGUUAAUCAACACGAGACCAGUACAAGCAAAUCUGUUUUUGAGCCUGAAGAUUCUUCAAUAGUAGAUAAUGAGUUGUGGUCAGAAAUGAGAAGACAUGAAAUGUUGAGGGAGGAGCUGCGACAGAGAAGAAAGCAGCUUGAAGCUCUGAUGGCUGAACAUCAGAGGAGGCAAGGUCUAGCUGAAACUGCAUCUCCAGUGGCUGUGUCAUUGAGAAGUGAUGGAUCUGAGAACCUAUGUACUCCUCAGCAAAGUAGAACAGAAAAAACGAUGGCAACUUGGGGAGGGUCUACCCAGUGUGCACUAGAUGAAGAAGGAGAUGAAGACGGUUACCUUUCUGAAGGAAUUGUUCGGACAGAUGAAGAGGAGGAAGAAGAGCAAGAUGCCAGUUCCAAUGAUAACUUUUCUGUGUGUCCUUCUAACAGUGUGAAUCAUAACUCCUACAAUGGAAAGGAAACUAAAAAUAGGUGGAAGAACAAUUGCCCUUUUUCGGCAGAUGAAAAUUAUCGUCCUUUAGCCAAGACAAGGCAACAGAAUAUCAGCAUGCAACGGCAAGAAAACCUUCGUUGGGUGUCAGAGCUCUCUUACGUAGAAGAGAAAGAACAAUGGCAAGAACAAAUCAAUCAGCUAAAGAAACAGCUUGAUUUUAGUGUCAGUAUUUGUCAGACUUUGAUGCAAGACCAGCAGACUCUAUCUUGUCUGCUACAAACUCUUCUCACGGGUCCUUACAGUGUUAUGCCCAGCAAUGUUGCAUCUCCUCAAGUACACUUCAUAAUGCACCAGUUGAACCAGUGCUAUACUCAGCUAACAUGGCAACAGAAUAAUGUUCAGAGGUUGAAACAAAUGCUAAAUGAACUUAUGCGCCAGCAAAAUCAGCAUCCAGAAAAACCUGGAGGCAAGGAAAGAGGCAGUAGUGCAUCGCACCCUCCUUCUCCCAGUUUAUUUUGUCCUUUCAGCUUUCCAACACAGCCUGUAAAUCUCUUCAAUAUACCUGGAUUUACUAACUUUUCAUCAUUUGCACCAGGUAUGAAUUUCAGCCCUUUAUUUCCUUCUAAUUUUGGAGAUUUUUCUCAGAAUAUCUCUACACCCAGUGAACAGCAGCAACCCUUAGCCCAGAAUUCUUCAGGAAAAACAGAAUAUAUGGCUUUUCCAAAACCUUUUGAAAGCAGUUCCUCUAUUGGAGCAGAGAAACCAAGGAAUAAAAAACUGCCUGAAGAGGAGGUGGAAAGCAGUAGGACACCAUGGUUAUAUGAACAAGAAGGUGAAGUAGAGAAACCAUUUAUCAAGACUGGAUUUUCAGUGUCUGUAGAAAAAUCUACAAGUAGUAACCGCAAAAAUCAAUUAGAUACAAACGGAAGAAGACGCCAGUUUGAUGAAGAAUCACUGGAAAGCUUUAGCAGUAUGCCUGAUCCAGUAGAUCCAACAACAGUGACUAAAACAUUCAAGACAAGAAAAGCGUCUGCACAGGCCAGCCUGGCAUCUAAAGAUAAAACUCCCAAGUCAAAAAGUAAGAAGAGGAAUUCUACUCAGCUGAAAAGCAGAGUUAAAAACAUCAGGUAUGAAAGUGCCAGUAUGUCUAGCACAUGUGAACCUUGCAAAAGUAGGAACAGACAUUCAGCCCAGACUGAAGAGCCUGUUCAAGCAAAAGUAUUCAGCAGAAAGAAUCAUGAGCAACUGGAAAAAAUAAUAAAAUGUAAUAGGUCUACAGAAAUAUCUUCAGAAACUGGGAGUGAUUUUUCCAUGUUUGAAGCUUUGCGAGAUACUAUUUAUUCUGAAGUAGCUACAUUAAUUUCUCAAAAUGAAUCUCGUCCACAUUUUCUUAUUGAACUCUUCCAUGAGCUGCAGCUACUAAACACAGACUACUUGAGACAGAGGGCUUUAUAUGCAUUGCAGGACAUAGUAUCCAGACAUAUUUCUGAGAGCCAUGAAAAAGGAGAAAAUGUAAAGUCAGUAAACUCUGGUACUUGGAUAGCAUCAAACUCAGAACUUACUCCUAGUGAGAGCCUUGCUACUACUGAUGAUGAAACUUUUGAGAAGAACUUUGAAAGAGAAACCCAUAAAAUAAGUGAGCAAAAUGAUGCUGAUAAUGCUAGUGUCCUGUCUGUAUCAUCAAAUUUUGAGCCUUUUGCAACAGAUGAUCUAGGUAACACCGUGAUUCACUUAGAUCAAGCAUUAGCCAGAAUGAGAGAAUAUGAGCGUAUGAAGACUGAGGCUGAAAGUAACUCAAAUAUGAGAUGCACCUGCAGGAUUAUUGAGGAUGGAGAUGGUGCUGGUGCAGGUACUACAGUUAAUAAUUUAGAAGAAACUCCCGUUAUUGAAAAUCGUAGUUCACAACAACCUGUAAGUGAAGUUUCUACCAUCCCAUGUCCUAGAAUUGAUACUCAGCAGCUGGACCGGCAAAUUAAAGCAAUUAUGAAAGAAGUCAUUCCUUUUUUGAAGGAGCACAUGGAUGAAGUAUGCUCCUCGCAGCUUCUAACUUCAGUAAGGCGCAUGGUUUUGACCCUUACCCAGCAAAAUGAUGAGAGCAAAGAGUUUGUAAAGUUCUUUCAUAAACAACUUGGAAGUAUAUUACAGGAUUCACUGGCAAAAUUUGCUGGCAGAAAACUGAAAGACUGUGGAGAAGAUCUUCUUGUAGAGAUAUCUGAAGUGUUGUUCAAUGAAUUGGCUUUCUUUAAGCUUAUGCAAGAUUUGGAUAAUAAUAGUAUAACUGUUAAACAGAGAUGCAAAAGGAAAAUAGAAGCAACUGGAGUGAUACAAUCUUGUGCCAAAGAGGCUAAAAGGAUUCUUGAAGAUCAUGGCUCACCUGCUGGAGAGAUUGAUGAUGAAGACAAAGACAAGGAUGAAACUGAAACAGUUAAGCAGACUCAAACAUCUGAGGUGUAUGAUGGUCCCAAAAAUGUAAGAUCUGAUAUUUCUGAUCAAGAGGAAGAUGAAGAAAGUGAAGGAUGUCCAGUGUCUAUUAAUUUGUCUAAAGCUGAAACUCAGGCUUUAACUAAUUAUGGAAGUGGAGAAGAUGAAAAUGAGGAUGAAGAAAUGGAAGAAUUUGAAGAAGGCCCUGUGGAUGUCCAGACUUCCCUCCAGGCUAACACUGAAGCUACUGAAGAAAAUGAACAUGAUGAACAGGUCCUACAACGUGACUUUAAAAAGACAGCAGAAAGCAAAAAUGUCCCAUUGGAACGAGAAGCCACUAGUAAAAAUGACCAAAAUAACUGUCCUGUGAAACCCUGUUACCUCAAUAUCUUGGAAGAUGAGCAACCUUUAAAUAGUGCUGCCCAUAAGGAGUCACCUCCUACUGUUGAUUCAACUCAACAGCCUAACCCUUUGCCGUUACGUUUACCUGAAAUGGAACCCUUAGUGCCUAGAGUCAAAGAAGUUAAAUCUGCUCAGGAAACUCCUGAAAGCUCUCUGGCUGGAAGUCCUGAUACUGAAUCUCCAGUGUUAGUGAAUGACUAUGAAGCAGAAUCUGGUAAUAUAAGUCAAAAGUCUGAUGAAGAAGAUUUUGUAAAAGUUGAAGAUUUACCACUGAAACUGACAAUAUAUUCAGAGGCAGAUCUAAGAAAGAAAAUGGUAGAAGAAGAACAGAAAAACCAUUUAUCUGGUGAAAUAUGUGAAAUGCAGACCGAAGAAUUAGCUGGAAAUUCUGAGACACUAAAAGAACCUGAAACGGUGGGAGCCCAGAGUAUAUGAGAUGUCUUCAGAGGCUCAUCUAACUCUGUCCUUACAUACUCAAUGCAUAUAUGAAAACAAUACUAAAUAAACAUCUGAUCUGUAUAAAAAUGUAAAUUAGUUUGACACUGCUUUUUUGAUAGGUGUGGUCAUUUCUCCCCAUGGUAGUUUAAAACAUCAGAAACUGAAUUCUGGACAGAUUUAAGCCUUGACACACUGUGUUUUUUUUUUUUUCCCCCUUCUUUUUUGGGUCUUCAUUUUUUUCCCCAUUGUGAUGUUUGGUAACGAAUUUAAAAUGUAGUUUUAAAUAAAGUUUGGACUUAUCUAUAAAGUAUCUUUUUUGGAAAUUAUAUUGAAUUCUAUACAGCAAGUCAAUGUUUUAUAUAACUUUAGGCUGCUCAGAGAAGAGCAAUGGUUAAGAGUUAGUUAGAGAAAUAUAUUAUUUGUUAUAAAGCCCAUCCAUUAGGCCAGUCUUCCAACUAAUGCCAGUGUUGCUGCUGUUGGGUCUGAUGUUCUUCUUUUAGAUACCUGCAGGUCCUAUUCCUGUGCAAGAAUAGGGCAGAUUAUCAAGAUAUCCAGGAUACCUAUGAAGUUAUUAUAGAAUAUUUAUUAAUCCAUUGAAAUUGGAUAAUAAGUUUAGAACAUAGGUUCUCAGUAUCUAGAACUUACAUCAUUAUCAUCUGUUUGUUAGGAUUUGAAAUUCUGGAAAAUAUUUAUCUACAUCGCCUCAGACUAAAAGUAAAAAAAAUAAGCUUUAUAUAAUUAGGGAGAUUUCUGCACAGAGAAGUAACAUUGUGGUUAAUUUUAAAUGAAAAACUUAACUUUUUCAAGUGGGGAUAAAUAAUACAACUAAAUUUCUGUAAUAGUAAGAUUCUGUAUGCCUUCAGAUAAACUUGCCUAUUGAGAUGGUAAUUUAAAGCCAAAGCAUAGCAGUUUCUUUUGUGUGUAGUGAGGUUGAAGCAGAUUUGCAGGUGAAGUAUUGAAAGUUUAUGUGACUUUAAGUCAGCUUUUGAAAAGUGAUUGAUUUGCUUUUUAUCCCAAACUGUCCAUAUACCCAGUAAGGCUUCAAAAAACCAGUCAACAAUGAGUAAGUCAAUCUUAUAGAUUCUUCUUCCUCGAAUAAAAUACAAAGAAUUAGUUCCAAUAAGUAUUUUAACUUUGUUAACAACUGAAAUACCCCAUAAAAAAAGAACUUGUUGAGAGUAUUUCUUUAAAAUGGUUACUUGCUGCCCAGGCACCAUGGCUCACUCCUGUAAUCCCAGCACCUUGGGAGGCCGAGGCGGGCAGAUCACGAGGUCAAGAGAUUGAGACCAUCCUGCCCAACAUGGGGGAAACCCCGUCUCUACUAAAAAUAAAAAAAUUAGCUGGGAGAGGUGGCACGUGCCUGUAGUCCUAGCUACUUGGGAGGCUAAGGCAGGAGAAUAGCCUGAACCCGGGAGGUGGAGGUUGCAGGUUGCAGUGAGCCGAGAUCAUGCCACUGCACUCCAGCCUGGCAACAGAGCGAGACUCUGUCUCAAAAAAAAAAAAAAAAAAAAAAAAAAGUUAACUUGCUGUAUACCUCAGUGUAAUGUCCAUUCAAGGAGUAUUAAAUGAGGAUUUCCCUGCGAGGACAUUUACUGUAUUGCUACUUAAAUUAUGGAAGACAAUAUAUCUUCAACUUUAAUAAAACCUAUUCAGAAAAUUACCAAUUCAGAAUUCGGAGUUCUUAUCCAGGUGCUCUAACUAACUUCAGGGAAAUUGGAACAAUAAGUUAUGUUACAUGCACACUCAAAUUCUUUAUUUUCUCCACUUUAAGCAGGAAAGGGUAAAAACUGUUUUGGUACUCAAGCCCAGCCUUACAUACUGUGUUUCUCUCUCUGUCUGCAUGCAUAUUAAAGUGGAAAAAUUGUAUUUAUAUCUUAGUUAUUACCAUAGUACCUAUGAACCUUAUCAAAAUUGCUUAUUUGACUGGUGUUACAGCUGCUAUUAAUCUAAGUCUAUUGUUUUUCUAUUUUAGUAGAUAAUUUAGUUUUAAAAUACGUAGGGUUUGAGAGCAGAUAUAUUUAUUUAAUCUGUUUUCUCUAGUAACUAUUGCUGAAGGGUUAGGCAUUCAGUAUUCCUAUUUGUCCUAAUUUUGAAGUUAAAAAUUUUGGUUACAGAUAGAUAGAGGGAGAAAAGUUCAAAAUGAGUGAGAGAGAACUUUAUGCAGGUUGAGAUAAUGCCUAAAAUAAUGAGCUGGCCAGACUGUGGAGGUACUCUUUGUAUUUUGUAACAUUGACUUUGGGUAAAUGCUUUUUCACUGUUAAUAAAUAUAUAUCCUGUAUACAA